CUCUCUCGGCCCGGCCAUCUUGUGGGAAGAGCUGAAGCAGGCGCUCUUGGCUCGGCGCGGCCCGCUGCAAUCCGUGGAGGAACGCGCCGCCGAGCCACCAUCAUGCCUGGGCACUUACAGGAAGGCUUCGGCUGCGUGGUCACCAACCGAUUCGACCAGUUAUUUGACGACGAAUCGGACCCCUUCGAGGUGCUGAAGGCAGCAGAGAACAAGAAAAAAGAAGCCGGCGGGGGCGGCGUUGGGGGCCCUGGGGCCAAGAGCGCAGCUCAGGCCGCGGCCCAGACCAACUCCAACGCGGCAGGCAAACAGCUGCGCAAGGAGUCCCAGAAAGACCGCAAGAACCCGCUGCCCCCCAGCGUUGGCGUGGUUGACAAGAAAGAGGAGACGCAGCCGCCCGUGGCGCUUAAGAAAGAAGGAAUAAGACGAGUUGGAAGAAGACCUGAUCAACAACUUCAGGGUGAAGGGAAAAUAAUUGAUAGAAGACCAGAAAGGCGACCACCUCGUGAACGAAGAUUCGAAAAGCCACUUGAAGAAAAGGGUGAAGGAGGCGAAUUUUCAGUUGAUAGACCGAUUAUUGACCGACCUAUUCGAGGUCGUGGUGGUCUUGGAAGAGGUCGAGGGGGCCGUGGACGUGGAAUGGGCCGAGGAGAUGGAUUUGAUUCUCGUGGCAAACGUGAAUUUGAUAGGCAUAGUGGAAGUGAUAGAUCUUCUUUUUCACAUUACAGUGGCCUGAAGCACGAGGACAAACGUGGAGGUAGCGGAUCUCACAACUGGGGAACUGUCAAAGACGAAUUAACAGAGUCCCCCAAAUACAUUCAGAAACAAAUAUCUUAUAAUUACAGUGACUUGGAUCAAUCAAAUGUGACUGAGGAAACACCUGAAGGUGAAGAACAUCAUCCAGUGGCAGACACUGAAAAUAAGGAGAAUGAAGUUGAAGAGGUAAAAGAGGAGGGUCCAAAAGAGAUGACUUUGGAUGAGUGGAAGGCUAUUCAAAAUAAGGACCGGGCAAAAGUAGAAUUUAAUAUCCGAAAACCAAAUGAAGGUGCUGAUGGGCAGUGGAAGAAGGGAUUUGUUCUUCAUAAAUCAAAGAGUGAAGAGGCUCAUGCUGAAGAUUCGGUUAUGGACCAUCAUUUCCGGAAGCCAGCAAAUGAUAUAACGUCUCAGCUGGAGAUCAAUUUUGGAGACCUUGGCCGCCCAGGACGUGGCGGCAGGGGAGGACGAGGUGGACGUGGGCGUGGUGGGCGCCCAAACCGUGGCAGCAGGACCGACAAGUCAAGUGCUUCUGCUCCUGAUGUGGAUGACCCAGAGGCAUUCCCAGCUCUGGCUUAACUGGAUGCCAUAAGACAACCCUGGUUCCUUUGUGAACCCUUCUGUUCAAAGCUUUUGCAUGCUUAAGGAUUCCAAACGACUAAGAAAUUAAAAAAAAAAAGACUGUCAUUCAUACCAUUCACACCUAAAGACUGAAUUUUAUCUGUUUUAAAAAUGAACUUCUCCCGCUACACAGAAGUAACAAAUAUGGUAGUCAGUUUUGUAUUUAGAAAUGUAUUGGUAGCAGGGAUGUUUUCAUAAUUUUCAGAGAUUAUGCAUUCUUCAUGAAUACUUUUGUAUUGCUGCUUGCAAAUAUGCAUUUCCAAACUUGAAAUAUAGGUGUGAACAGUGUGUACCAGUUUAAAGCUUUCACUUCAUUUGUGUUUUUUAAUUAAGGAUUUAGAAGUUCCCCCAAUUACAAACUGGUUUUAAAUAUUGGACAUACUGGUUUUAAUACCUGCUUUGCAUAUUCACACAUGGUCAACUGGGACAUGUUAAACUUUGAUUUGUCAAAUUUUAUGCUGUGUGGAAUACUAACUAUAUGUAUUUUAACUUAGUUUUAAUAUUUUCAUUUUUGGGGAAAAAUCUUUUUUCACUUCUCAUGAUAGCUGUUAUAUAUAUAUGCUAAAUCUUUAUAUACAGAAAUAUCAGUACUUGAACAAAUUCAAAGCACAUUUGGUUUAUUAACCCUUGCUCCUUGCAUGGCUCAUUAGGUUCAAAUUAUAACUGAUUUACAUUUUCAGCUAUAUUUACUUUUUAAAUGCUUGAGUUUCCCAUUUUAAAAUCUAAACUAGACAUCUUAAUUGGUGAAAGUUGUUUAAACUACUUAUUGUUGGUAGGCACAUCGUGUCAAGUGAAGUAGUUUUAUAGGUAUGGGUUUUUUCUCCCCCUUCACCAGGGUGGGUGGAAUAAGUUGAUUUGGCCAAUGUGUAAUAUUUAAACUGUUCUGUAAAAUAAGUGUCUGGCCAUUUGGUAUGAUUUCUGUGUGUGAAAGGUCCCAAAAUCAAAAUGGUACAUCCAUAAUCAGCCACCAUUUAACCCUUCCUUGUUCUAAAACAAAAACCAAAGGGCGCUGGUUGGUAGGGUGAGGUGGGGGAGUAUUUUAAUUUUUGGAAUUUGGGAAGCAGACAGCUUUACUUUGUAAGGUUGGAACAGCAGCACUAUACAUGAAAUAUAAACCAAAAACCUUUACUGUUUCUAAAUUUCCUAGAUUGCUAUUAUUUGGUUGUAAGUUGAGUAUUCCACAGAAAGUGGUAAUUAUCUCUUCUCUCUUCCUCCAUUAGAAAAUUAGGUAAAUAAUGGAUUCCUAUAAUGGGAGCAUCACCACUUAUUAAAACACACAUAGAAUGAUGAAUUAAAAAAGUUUUCUAGGAUUGUCUUUUAUUCUGCCACAUUUAUUGAUAAACAGUGAAGGAAUUUUUAAAAAAUUUUUAAGAAUUGUUUGUCACGUCAUUUUUAGAAAUGUUCUACCUGUAUAUGGUAAUGUCCAGUUUUAAAAAUAUUGGACAUCUUCAAUCUUAAACAUUUCUAUUUAGCUGAUUGGUUCUCACAUAUACUUCUAAAAGAAACUUUUAUGUUAUAAGAGUUACUUUUUGGAUAAGAUUUAUUAAUCUCAGUUACCUACUAUUCUGACAUUUUAGGAAGGAGGUAAUUGUUUUUAAUGAUGGAUAAACUUGUGCUGGUGUUUUGGAUCUUAUGAUGCUGAGCAUGUUCUGCACUGGUGCUAAUGUCUAAUAUAAUUUUAUAUUUACACACAUACGUGCUACCCAGAGAUUAAUUUAGUCCAUAUGAACUAUUGACCCAUUGUUCAUUGAGACAGCAACAUACGCACUCCUAAAUCAGUGUGUUUAGACUUUUCAAGUAUCUAACUCAUUUCCAAACAUGUACCAUGUUUUAUAAACCUCUUGAUUUCCAGCAACAUACUAUAGAAAACACCUGCUACUCAAAACACAACUUCUCAGUGUCAUCCAUUGCUGUCGUGAGAGACAACAUAGCAAUAUCUGGUAUGUUGCAAGCUUUCAAGAUAGCCUGAACUUAAAAAGUUGGUGCAUUAGUUGUAUCUGAUGGAUAUAAAUUUGCCUCCUAGUUCACUUUGUGUCAAGAGCUAAAACUGUGAACCUAACUUUCUCUUAUUGGUGGGUAAUAACUGAAAAUAAAGAUUUAUUUUCAUGCUCACUUCUUAAAAGUCAUAAAAACAAUCAAAUAGGAUCAUGUUUAUUGUCAUGUGUUUCCUGGUUUCUGACCUGUGUGCACACCCCUGUGUGUUUAUAAUUUUUAAAUUGAAUUUUAUAUGGGGUUUUUAUUUGCUAAAAACCAGGCUGUUGAAUCACAUUUGGGAAGGGUACUUAUCUUAAUGACUAAUGACUUAAUUGGGAAAGUUGAAUUCUUGUAAAAUACAAAAUCCAAGGACUUCUUGGAUUUAAUCUGAUUGUCACUUCUUAGCAGAUCACUUUUUUGAUAAUGAAAGUUAAGCAUACUGAAUGCUACUUUUGAUUGACAAACUGGCUAUAAUAGUCUAGGGGAAAAAUCCCUAAACAGAUAAAGAUUCCUAAAGUAAUGGUGGCAGCUGAUGUUUCAGUGAACUUUUAUCUUGAUGCGUUUAAAUGGAAGUAAUGCCAGACCUGAGAUUUUUAAGGCAUUUUUACAGCUUGUAUUGAAAUGAUUGGAGACAUGGUUUCUUUAUUAGCUAUUUUGAGACCUGUGGAGUUAAGCAAGACUUUUAAAAAUUGGCACCAUAUACAUCUAGUUAGUUCCUUUACUCUUAUUUUUUUAAAUAAAAGUAGUACACAUCAUUUCCAGGGUUGUAAAUAUAUUUGGGGCUUGUUUUUGGUAUGGAUUUAAAAGGAGGAUAUUAAGUAUUCAUUCUAAUUUUGUUAUUUUUCUAGUUGCCAGAGAUGGUUGCACUGAAAUAGAACAGGGAGUUGCAUACAAAGCCUAAAUGUGUAUUGGAUUUCGAAAAUACUAGGUUGGUGCAAUUGGUUUUGUACCAACCUAACAUGUCUUUAGGAAAGUACCAUCAUGUGGAAGGAAACAACAGGUGUUAAAAGGUUCAAAGGAAUGAGAAAUAGGAAGUUACUAGAACCUAACUGAUGUUGACCUUAGAGGUAAGAUUAUUCAGGUAUAUUAGUGGACCUCCAGUCCAAUGGUAUAGCAAAUUCCAGGGAUCUCAGGUGCAUGCAAUUUUACUUUCUAAAGUAAACACUUAGAAAAUAGAUUAUAACCCAGACGUUUUGGAUUAUACUGAGACAAAUAUGUAAAUAAGUUUUAGCAAGUCUGAACAUGUACCAGCGAGAUCUUCAGGUUAACUAAGAAAAGCCCAGAAACUUCAUUAUUUACUGUGCUUUGUAUGGCAUAACUGGUAACAAGGCAGUAAAAUGAUACAUAUUUGAACUGGACCAUAGUAAUUAAAUGAUUUAUCAAUAUCAUUUGCAAGAUAAUUGUCAGGUUGAGUUAAUAGUAAGUGGCAGCUUCCCAGAAAUUUGGGUUAUUUGGCCUAAGCUGUGCCCUGGGAUUACCUCUUCAUCUUCCUUGACUUUUAAGUUCAAAUUUGGAGGUUAUGUGAAGUGAUUGAAAUAAAUCUUUCAGGCUGAGGAAGUCGGUAAUUUCAAGAAUAUAGUGAAAACAAGGUUGUAAUCUAAACAUGAGAAGCUUAAGUUUAGGAAAUGGUUAGAAUAUAAAUUGCUAAAGCCAUCAUGAUUUUGGCCACAGAUGAAAAUAUGAACACUGGAAAUGAGCGCCAUUUAAAUGAGAUGCUGUAUGUAAGCCAGGGGUCAGCAAAGUUCAGCCUGUGACCUGGUGUGUGUGGGGGUGUGUGUGUGUGUGUGUGUGUGUGUGUGUGUGUCCGUGUCCCUGAGUUAAGAAUGGUUUUUAGGCUUGUAUAGGAUUAAAAAAAAAAAAAACCCACAGAAAAAUGUAGGCAGCCCAGCAUAAGAUACCGCCUUUCACAGAAAUGUUUGCUGACCCCGGAACUGUCACUCUCGGGUUACAAGAGUUUGUUUCUUUGAAACAGUCUGGCUCUGUCACCCAGGCUGGAGUGCAGUGGCAUGAUCUCAGGUCACUGCAGCCUCCACCUCCCGGGUUCAAGCAAUUCUGCCUCAGCCUCCUGAGUAGCUGGGAUUACAGGUGUGCACCACCACAGACAGCUAAUUUUACAGGUGUACACCACCACACCCAAGAAUCACUUGAACCCGGGAGGUGGGGGUUGCAGUGAGCCAAGAUCAUAGCACUGUACUCCAGUCUGGGUGACACACUGUCUGAAAAAUAAAAGUUUAGUUCUAGGUACAAAUUAAGUGGUCUACCCAACAGGAAGCUGUGAAAUUAGAAGUAAUUUUAAAGCAUACUUUACACCUCUAUAUAAUCAAAGUAAGGGCAAGAUAAAACUUGUUAGUAAAACAUGUUUUAUUAUUUUUUAGAUAGGUAGCCUGCAACAUAAAAUAUAUUUUGAAAGCUGUUAAGGGGUGUAUAAUCUGUUAAAAAAUACCAUGAUUAGUAUUUCACAUUUAGUGACUCAGAUCCCUUUGUGUAAGUCCUUUGCGUUGUGCAAAGAGGUUUUUCUAUGAGAUGAGAAUUAUGAACACUUCAUAUAGGUAAAUUCCAUAGGUUGAGCUGGGGCAGAAAUUAAUGGCUCCUGGAGAUUGCAUCUUUUUUUUUUUUUUUUUGAGCUUAGAAUUCCCAUUUGGACAGAAUUUAGCUUUUGUGCUGUUGAUUACUUCUGUACUAAACUGGUAGCCAAUUGUUCACUUCUAAAUGGAAGGGAAAAAGUUACCCACACAAGUUAGAAAAUGAUUUACCGAAUUAUUUUUUUGAGUUAGUAUGUAUAUACUGUUUUAAAUCAGUAAUGUUUGUUCCUUUUGCUGCCCAUUUGGGAGUAUGUGGCAAUUCCUAGUGCUCUUGUAUGACAUUACUCUUCUUGAGACUUGUAUAUGCAAGAAAGUAUAUAUAAAAGAUGCCUGGUGGUAACUUUGUAUCUGAGUUCUGAUUCAUUAUGGACUUUUAGAAAUCUAUUUAGAUAAUUGGUUCAUACUAGGUGCUCAAUUACUCUGACCUUGUGUGGCUUAAUCCUUAAAUAGUUGCUUUAGGUGUUACUGGGUGGAAGCAUGGAAAGUGAAGGGCUAAUAUUAAGGAUUUUUAUGUAUUACUGAGUAGGGAAAGUGGGAAGUAGCUUAUCUUUGGACAGUUGUAUUACUUUGCACUAAUCACCUUGUUUGCAGUUGUAGCUGAUUCAGUUCUAGAUUUUAGGACCAAAAAGAUCUCUAAUUUAAAGAAACAGUUUUUAUAUACCUAGAAUGAAGAUUCUGUUUAAAGCGGUUUUGGUUAACUUGGUUCUUGACAUUUGCCUAAAAUUUUGUUGGAUUGGGACUAAAAUGUUCUAUUAGCCAAUGAAUAACGUCCAAGUAAAUUUUUGUUUUAUUUUGGGAA